GAAGCCAACAAGAAUUUGAGAACUGUAAAUACCAAGCCUUGAAAGGGACCAUGGUGCGGCCUGUGAGACAUAAGAAACCAGUCAAUUACUCACAGUUUGACCACUCUGACAGUGAUGAUGAUUUUGUUUCUGCAACUGUACCUUUAAACAAGAAAUCCAGAACAGCACCAAAGGAGUUAAAACAAGAUAAACCAAAACCUAACUUGAACAAUCUCCGGAAAGAAGAAAUCCCAGUACAAGAGAAAACCCCUAAAAAAAGACUCCCUGAAGGUACUUUUAGUAUUCCAGCUAGUGCAGUGCCUUGUACAAAGAUGGCUUUAGAUGACAAGCUCUACCAGAGAGACUUAGAAGUUGCACUAGCUUUAUCAGUGAAGGAACUUCCAACAGUCACCACUAAUGUGCAGAACUCUCAAGAUAAAAGCAUUGAAAAACAUGGCAGUAGUAAAAUAGAAACAAUGAAUAAGUCUCCUCAUAUCUCUAAUUGCAGUGUAGCCAGUGAUUAUUUAGAUUUGGAUAAGAUUACUGUGGAAGAUGAUGUUGGUGGUGUUCAAGGGAAAAGAAAAGCAGCAUCUAAAGCUGCAGCACAGCAGAGGAAGAUUCUUCUGGAAGGCAGUGAUGGUGAUAGUGCUAAUGACACUGAACCAGACUUUGCACCUGGUGAAGAUUCUGAGGAUGAUUCUGAUUUUUGUGAGAGUGAGGAUAAUGACGAAGACUUCUCUAUGAGAAAAAGUAAAGUUAAAGAAAUUAAAAAGAAAGAAGUGAAGGUAAAAUCCCCAGUAGAAAAGAAAGAGAAGAAAUCUAAAUCCAAAUGUAAUGCUUUGGUGACUUCGGUGGACUCUGCUCCAGCUGCCGUCAAAUCAGAAUCUCAGUCCUUGCCAAAAAAGGUUUCUCUGUCUUCAGAUACCACUAGGAAACCAUUAGAAAUACGCAGUCCUUCAGCUGAAAGCAAGAAACCUAAAUGGGUCCCACCAGGUAUGGCAUAUUUAUCAUCAAGGACAGGAGCUUGGAAAAUUAUCACUGCGGCAUCUGGAGGUAGCAGAAGUAGCAGCAGCCCACUGGUGGUAGUGUCUGUGAAGUCUCCCAAUCAGAGUCUCCGCCUUGGCUUGUCCAGAUUAGCACGAGUUAAACCUUUGCAUCCAAAUGCCACUAGCACCUGAGUGUGGUACAGGAGGAAUGUUUGGUUGGGAGAAUCACAGCUUUACAAGGGUGUUUAUAUUUGAUUUGUGUUUAUAUUUGAGGCAGGUAUUGUAAUAUAAAGGAAUCCAUUACCAUGUCCUAUAAAUGACCUCUAGCCAUUUUAUGAUUAUGUUCUCUGUAAAACUCUUCAAGACUUCAAUGAGAAGUUUGUUUAUAAGAAUUAUCUUCUCAUACCUUUCCUUGUGAAGAGCGUAUUCUGUUUUUCUAUCAGUUCGACAUGAAGUCCACAUCACAUGCUGUUCUUUUCUAGUUACAUGAUGUGCCUUUCUAGCUUUGUCUAGUUUAUAGCACCUUAACUUUAACUGUUCAGUUUUAUCUGGCAGAGGAAAACAUUCUUAUUUCUUUCAGAAGACAUUUCUGAAAUCUUAUAAGCUACUUAAGCUACGUUGUCAGUUUUAUCGCAAAGAUGUUUUGUAUUUUAGCCAAAUCUUUUUAUAGUACAAACUUAGAAUUAUUUUACACACUAAAAUGGUUGCAGUUUUAUGGCAUAUGUCUCCGAUUUAGAUGGUUAUUCUCUAGAAAAUAGUAUUUAAAGACAUUUUAUGAAAUCUUCAUUGUCAAAACCUUUAAUAAAAGUGGAAAUAUUUUGAAAUGCCCUUUUUCUUGAUACCACUCAUCCACGUGUUCCUGAUUGUCCACAUUUCAUGAUAAAAUGAGAGCUCCGCAGAGAAUGUUAGCCUUUCUGUUGUAAAUGUAAUCUUCAAGUAGUCACUUUUUGUUAAGUUCUUUAGAAAGUAGUUGUCAAGUACUUAGUCAUCCCUAUUAUGAUAUGAGAUAGUACAGCUUUUCAGGAAGCUUAGAUCUGAAUUUACUUUGAAAAACAAUUGUAAUGAAUAUUUUAUAUUUACAUUGAGAAUUUCAACUAGCUUCUGAUCAAUUUUUAAUAAAAAAUUUUCAAAUCAUGUUAGCUGUUAAAAAAUGUAUAAUAACUCAGUUUUUCUUGGUUUAUGGAAAUAUCUAUAUUAAUGUGAAAAUAAUUAAUUUAGAAUUGUGAUUAAAGUGAGCAUUUGUCUA